AUGUGUCCCUUGACCUUGCAGGUCACUGGCCUAAUGAAUGUCUCUGAGCCAAAUUCCAGCUUUGCUUUUGUAAAUGAAUUUAUACUCCAAGGUUUCACUUGUGAGUGGACAAUUCAGAUCUUCCUCUUCUCACUCUUUACUACAACAUAUGCACUGACUAUAACAGGGAAUGGAGCCAUUGCUUUUGUCCUGUGGUGUGACUGGCGACUUCACACUCCCAUGUACAUGUUCCUGGGAAAUUUCUCCUUUUUAGAGAUAUGGUAUGUCUCUUCUACAGUUCCCAAGAUGUUGGUCAACUUCCUUUCAGAGAAAAAAAACAUCUCCUUUGCUGGAUGUUUUCUCCAGUUUUAUUUCUUCUUCUCUUUGGGUACAUCAGAAUGCUUGCUUUUGACUGUGAUGGCCUUUGAUCAGUACCUUGCUAUCUGCCGUCCCUUGCUCUAUCCUAAUAUCAUGACUGGGCAUCUCUGUGCCAAACUGGUCAUACUGUGCUGGGUUUGUGGAUUUCUGUGGUUCCUGAUCCCCAUUGUUCUCAUCUCUCAGAUGCCCUUCUGUGGCCCAAACAUUAUUGACCAUGUUGUGUGUGACCCAGGGCCACGAUUUGCAUUGGAUUGUGUUUCUGCCCCAAGAAUCCAACUGUUUUGCUACACUCUAAGCUCAUUAGUUAUUUUUGGUAACUUCCUCUUUAUUAUUGGAUCCUAUACUCUUGUCCUGAAAGCUGUGUUGGGUAUGCCUUCAAGCACUGGGAGACAUAAGGCCUUCUCUACCUGUGGGUCUCAUUUGGCUGUGGUAUCACUGUGCUAUAGCUCUCUUAUGGUCAUGUAUGUGAGCCCAGGACUCGGACAUUCUACAGGGAUGCAGAAAAUUGAAACUUUGUUCUAUGCUAUGGUGACCCCACUCUUCAAUCCCCUUAUCUAUAGCCUCCAGAAUAAGGAGAUAAAGGCAGCCCUGAGGAAAGUUCUGGGAAGUUCCAACAUAAUCUAA